AGUAGCUGGGGUGAGGCCGUCGUCGCCGCACGGGCUGGUUGGGGCUGUGUCUGUGGGAGGCGCCGGGGUGAUGGCGGUGGAGACUCUGUCCCCGGACUGGGAGUUUGACCGCGUUGACGACGGCUCGCAGAAAAUUCAUGCCGAAGUCCAACUUAAGAAUUAUGGGAAAUUUCUUGAGGAGUAUACCUCUCAACUGAGAAGAAUUGAGGACGCUCUGGAUGACUCAAUUGGAGAUGUUUGGGAUUUCAAUCUUGAUCCUAUAGCAUUAAAGCUUUUGCCUUAUGAACAGUCCUCUCUUUUGGAACUCAUAAAGACUGAAAACAAGGUCUUAAACAAAGUCAUCACUGUUUAUGCUGCACUUUGUUGUGAAAUCAAGAAAUUAAAAUAUGAGGCUGAAACUAAAUUUUACAAUGGUCUCUUGUUUUAUGGAGAAGGAGCUACAGAUGCCAGCAUGGUGGAAGGUGAUUGCCAAAUUCAAAUGGGGAGAUUUAUUUCAUUCUUACAGGAACUGUCUUGCUUUGUUACGAGGUGCUAUGAAGUGGUGAUGAACGUAGUCCACCAGUUGGCUGCCCUCUAUAUCAGUAACAAGAUUGCACCCAAAAUUAUAGAGACAACUGGAGUUCAUUUUCAGACUAUGUAUGAGCACUUGGGAGAACUGCUAACAGUUUUGCUCACCCUGGAUGAAAUUAUUGAUAAUCAUAUCACACUGAAAGACCACUGGACUAUGUACAAAAGGUUACUGAAAUCUGUCCAUCACAAUCCUUCAAAAUUUGGAAUUCAGGAAGAAAAAUUAAAGCCAUUUGAAAAGUUCUUGCUGAAGCUAGAAGGGCAAUUACUGGAUGGAAUGAUAUUCCAGGCCUGUAUAGAACAACAAUUUGAUUCUCUCAAUGGAGGAGUAUCUGUGUCAAAAAAUAGUACUUUUGCUGAGGAAUUUGCACAUAGUAUUCGGUCAAUUUUUGCAAAUGUAGAAGCCAAACUUGGAGAACCUUCUGAAAUUGACCAGAGAGACAAGUAUGUUGGAAUUUGUGGACUCUUUGUAUUGCACUUUCAGAUUUUUCGAACUAUUGAUAAAAAGUUUUAUAAGUCUUUAUUGGACAUUUGUAAGAAGGUACCAGCCAUCACUCUAACUGCUAAUAUUAUUUGGUUUCCUGAUAAUUUUCUGAUCCAGAAAAUACCAGCAGCUGCCAAACUGCUAGACAGAAAAAGUCUUCAAGCCAUUAAAAUACACAGGGAUACUUUUCUACAACAGAAAGCUCAAUCACUUACCAAAGAUGUACAGUCUUACUACGUCUUUGUGAGCUCAUGGAUGAUGAAAAUGGAAUCUAUUUUGUCUAAAGAGCAGAGAAUGGAUAAAUUUGCUGAAGAUCUCACCAAUAGAUGUAAUGUUUUUAUACAGGUAGGCUUCUUGUAUGCAUAUAGUAUUAGUACCAUUAUUAAAACCACAAUGAAUCUCUACAUGUCCAUGCAAAAGCCAAUGACCAAAACCUCAGUUAAGGCAUUGUGCAGGCUUGUUGAACUUCUCAAGGCAAUAGAGCAUAUGUUCUACAGGAGAAGCAUGGUUGUGGCUGAUUCAGUUUCACAUAUAACACAGCACCUUCAACAUCAGGCUCUUCAUUCUAUUUCUGUGGCCAAGAAAAGAGUGAUUUCUGACAAAAAAUACAGCGAACAGCGUCUUGAUGUGCUCUCUGCUCUAGUUUUGGCUGAAAACACUCUAAAUGGACCAAGCACAAAGCAACGGCGACUUAUUGUUUCUUUGGCACUAAGUGUUGGCACACAAAUGAAAACAUUUAAAGAUGAAGAACUCUUUCCACUUCAAGUAGUCAUGAAAAAACUGGAUCUUAUUAGUGAACUUAGAGAACGAGUCCAAACACAAUGUGACUGUUGUUUUUUAUACUGGCAUCGAGCUGUCUUCCCAAUUUAUUUAGAUGAUGUAUAUGAAAAUGCUGUUGAUGCAGCCAGAUUACAUUACAUGUUCAGUGCUUUGCGCGACUGUGUACCUGCUAUGAUGCAUGCAAGGCAUUUAGAGUCCUAUGAGAUACUUCUGGAUUGCUAUGACAAGGAAAUUAUGGAAAUUUUAAAUGAGCAUUUGCUGGACAAAUUAUGCAAAGAAAUAGAGAAAGAUCUGCGACUUUCUGUGCAUACUCAUUUAAAGCUGGAUGACCGAAACCCUUUCAAAGUUGGCAUGAAAGACCUGGCUCUUUUUUUCUCUCUGAAUCCAAUUCGGUUUUUCAAUCGUUUCAUUGACAUUCGGGCUUACGUAACUCACUACCUAGACAAGACUUUCUACAAUCUAACAACUGUAGCCCUUCAUGACUGGGCCACUUAUAGUGAGAUGAGAAACUUAGCUACUCAGCGUUAUGGACUGGUUAUGACAGAGGCACAUCUUCCCAGUCAGACUUUGGAACAGGGCCUUGAUGUUUUAGAAAUUAUGAGAAACAUUCAUAUAUUUGUGUCCCGAUACCUCUAUAAUCUCAACAAUCAGAUUUUUAUUGAACGAACAAGCAAUAACAAGCAUUUGAAUACUAUUAAUAUUCGGCAUAUUGCUAAUUCAAUUCGAACACAUGGCACGGGAAUUAUGAAUACAACUGUUAAUUUCACCUACCAGUUUUUGAAAAAGAAGUUCUAUAUAUUUAGCCAAUUUAUGUAUGAUGAACACAUCAAAUCCAGAUUGAUUAAAGAUAUUCGAUUUUUCAGGGAAAUUAAGGACCAAAAUGAUCAUAAGUAUCCUUUUGAUAGAGCAGAAAAAUUCAAUCGAGGCAUCAGAAAACUUGGAGUAACACCUGAGGGACAGAGCUACCUUGAUCAAUUCAGGCAACUCAUCAGCCAGAUUGGUAAUGCUAUGGGCUAUGUACGAAUGAUAAGAUCUGGUGGUCUUCAUUGUAGCAGCAAUGCCAUUAGAUUUGUUCCUGAUCUUGAAGAUAUUGUAAAUUUUGAAGAACUAGUAAAAGAAGAAGGUCUUGCAGAAGAAACAUUAAAAGCAGCAAGGCAUUUGGAUUCAGUCCUCAGUGAUCACACACGAAAUUCUGCCGAAGGCACAGAAUAUUUCAAAAUGCUUGUAGACGUUUUUGCUCCAGAAUUUCGAAGGCCAAAGAAUAUACAUCUCCGAAAUUUCUAUAUAAUUGUUCCCCCUCUGACCCUCAACUUUGUAGAGCAUUCCAUUAGUUGCAAGGAAAAAUUAAAUAAAAAAAAUAAAAUUGGAGCUGCCUUUACUGAUGAUGGCUUUGCCAUGGGUGUGGCUUACAUUCUAAAGCUUUUGGAUCAGUAUCGGGAGUUUGAUUCACUUCACUGGUUCCAGUCUGUUAGAGAGAAAUACCUGAAGGAGAUAAGAGCAGUUGCUAAGCAACAGAAUGUACAGUCAGCCAGUCAAGAUGAAAAACUCUUACAAACCAUGAAUCUCACUCAGAAGCGACUGGAUGUCUAUCUACAGGAAUUUGAAUUGCUGUAUUUCUCACUGAGCAGUGCAAGAAUUUUCUUCAGAGCAGACAAGACUGCGGCUGAAGAAAACCAAGAAAAGAAAGAGAAGGAAGAAGAAACUAAAACAAGCAAUGGAGACCUGUCUGACAGCACUGUGUCUGCUGAUCCUGUUGUGAAAUGAUACGGAUGGUAUUCACUGCACAUAUGAUGAAAUCAUCAGAAUUGUUAAAACUUUUGCCAGUGGAAUGGAUAAACUAUUGAUGAAUUGUUUCCUGGGUCACAUCUCUGGAAAAUAGAUGUUACAGUUCUUAAAGGCAGUGCUUUAAAGUGAAGUUCAUUCUGUUUCCAAAGGCUCUACUUUCAAAGGUUAAGAAUGAGAUUUUAAAAUUGGAUUUUUGCCUGGACUUGAGGGUACAAGAUGUUUCUAUUUGAAGUGAAGUUAUAAAAGGGCAAAUCCAGAUUCAUAAACUAUCACCUCGGAUUUCUUGUAAUCUACAUGUUUGUAAUUUGUAUUUGCAUAGAUCUUUGAUCUAUAGUUAUUUCAAGUCAUGGGAAAUUCAAUGCAUAUACUAUAUACAGCCAGUAAAUACAUGCUUAACAAAAGGAAUGAGCCUGAAGUUCAUAAAGAAUACAUAUCAAUAUUCUUAUAAAAGGAAUAUAUGAAGAUGGCUUUGAUACUAGAGGUGAGGCACAAGUGUUUUAUGUACUCUCAGUGUACAGUAUAACUGAUGAUCCUUCUUUCAUUGUUAAUUUCAUGUGACUCACAAGAGCUGCUGAUGUCUUUGAUGAGACAUUUUAUAACUAGUUUACAUUGCUUUGAGAACAUUUAACCUCCAACAGCUGCUUUAAAUUUAAGAUUUACUUAAUACUCAGAAAAUUCAGAUAAAGCCAUAGAGUCCUGUUUGAAGCUUCACUUCUAUUUUGGUUGAAGGCAUGAUGUAUGAUGUCAGAAAAAAAAUUGAAUGAAUUAUUUCUACAUCCAAACUCAGGUUUCUUCUACAUUAGAUUGAAUUGAAAUUUUGGUGAUGGUUUGGGUAGACUUUUUUUUUAUAUCAAGUAUAAUUUAAAACAUCAGAUUAAAUAAUUACACUGUUCAGGCUUUUAAAAAAAUACCACUGUGAGAAUAAAGCGCUAGCAAGAUACAUCACUUACUGAUUUUAAAAAUACAGAAAGAUUUUGAGUAAAUUUUGUGCCCAGCAAGCUGUUAGUUUUAUUUUUGUAAAGGUAUGUAAGUUAUUAAAUGGUUAAUCAUGGCCUUUUAAAAAUAAAAUAAAGUGAUACCUUUACAAUGAAGACAAAAGUUUAAAACUUUCUAAUACAAACACCAUUUUGGGAAAUGCUUGAUUUUUUUCUAUUGCAUUUGUCUGCUAAACAUUUCUUUGGAUAAAUCCUGCAAAUACUUCUAACAUUAUUCUUUGAUUCCAGCUUUUAGAAUGGGUGUACAAUGCCCUGUUUGUACUUACUGGUUAGGGUCAGGGUAACUUGCCAGCCCAAGAUAAAUACUUUAAUUGUUAAAAGUCAGAAGAGACAGAAUAUGUAGGAAAUGUUUUUUGUUUAUUAUGUAAACAUGGCUUACAGAAUUAUGAACAGUGGAUAGAUUAAAGGCAUUUAAUAUUUGUAAUUCAUAAUAACUGUAGAAAUGGCCCUAAAGCAUGCUGCAUAAUUAAUAAUUUAUAUUUUCAUUAUUAUAAGUGUUUAUAUUAAUGAUCUUGCAUUUGAUUAUAUCAAAUUCGUCAUUUCAUAGCAACAGUAUUGUUUUCUCUGUUUUUCUUCUCUAACUUCUCUGAAAUCAUCUCCUAUUAAGGGAUAGAAAUUGUUACUAGAAGAGAAUCACAUGUUCUGUGUUCAUUAUCCCUACACAUGUAAAUUAAUUAUUUUAUCAAUACUAGAUAGAGUUCACAUGCUGACUCCCUGGAUACCUACAGUUGAGAAGAAAAUGACAGACAAUUAUUUUUCCUUUAGGUCAAAAUAAUGUCACUGCUAUCUGGAUAAAUUAUAAGUUCAUAUAUUUGAAAUAAGAUCCUGGAAACGAAUUUAAAUGGUGUCAAACUGCAGAGCAACAGGGCUUCAGUAUAUUCACAUCUAAUAGGUUAAUAUGUACAUUUGGAUGAUGAUUUUUCUUGAUAACAUUAACAUUAAUUUUAUUUUUUCAGACAUACUGUAAUUUAAAAAUUAAUGUGAGCGUUUGUUUUAAGUUCACAGAAAACUUAAUAAUUCAAAUUCUCAGGAAUUAAGGACUCACCAUAACAUUGUCAGUUCUAAUGAAAUUUUGUAAAAGAUGGCAAGUUUGUUACCUCACUUGAGUGGGGUUUUCCUUUUCCCCCAAUUCUAAGAGAAUAUAAUGUGUAUACUAAAACAUUAAUAAACAUAAUUUUGAAAA